ACACCCGUCCUAGUCGAAGUCGAGAUUUCCUUUGGCUUCAAAGCUCUCUCACCAUAUUUUGGGAAGUUAUGGAUCAUCACAUUCCCAUGCAUGCGUUGCCUGAAGAAAUCCAAAAGAUGUUGCCUGAAGAAAAAGUUUGUAAGUACUGUGGAGUCAGCUAUCUAAUUCUUCAUGAAUUUAAGGCUAUGGAAGAAAAAGUGAAAGCAAUGGAAAAAGAGAUGAAAUUUUAUCAAGGAAGUGUAGAUCGUGAAAAGAGACUUCAAGAAAAGCUGCAUUCUCUUAGCCAAGAACUUGAACAGUACAAAAUUGACAACAAAUCCAAAACAGAAAGAAUUUACGAUGUAGGCAUGCAGUUAAAAAGUCAACAAAAUGAAUUUCAGAAAGUAAAGAAACAACUGAGUCAUUUGCAAGAUGAGCUAAAAAUUAAAUAUAGACAAUCAUACAUCUUCAGUCAAAGAUUGUCAGAGUACAAAUAUUUCUGGAAUAAGACUCUUUCAUUACUUACUUUUACUAAAAGGGAACUAACCAGUAUUAAAAAUGAAGUAUAUGAUAAUUACCAAAACUGGACUUCAUUGAAAGGAGCAGUUUUUCUACAAAUUAAAUCUAUAAGUGAAACAGCCUUGACAGAAAUAGACAUACUGAAUAAAAGUUUGACAGUAUCCCAGAGAAAUAAAGUAUGCCUUGAAAAGGAAAUGAAAAAUCUGAAAUUGUUGUCAGAUGCAGCCAUAUUGAGAUCUCAGCAGAUUCGGACAUCUAGACAACAGGAAGUAAACUUGCAAACCAGAUGCUAUGAUUUGCAAAAAGAAGUACUAGAUUUACAAUGUCUAGUAGAGGCACUUGGAUUAAAACUUCAGAAGGCGGUGACAGAGAUGGACAACUAUAAAGAAAUGCUUAUGAAUAAAUCUAAUGAAGCUGAUGACUGUCAAAGAGAACUUAAAAAACUGAAGUUUGAAUCCAUUAUUUCUGAGUCACAGCAUACUAUGCUGCUUAAGGAAAAAGAAGACUCUUUAAUGACUUGUCAACAGAUAUAUAAAGCAUUACAGGAAGAGCUGACUGUGAAAGAAAAGCAAGAAGAAGACAUAAAGAGAAGAAUUAACCUUGCAGAAAAUGAACUGGAGAUAACCAAAACUCUUCUGAAUCAGACAAGGGAAGAGGUUUUAACACUGAAAAAUGAAAGGGAAUUGAUGCUGAUUUCACAUCAGAAAAGCAUCGAGCAGCUGCAAGAAACCCUUAGACAGAAGCUGCUGAGUGAUGAUAACUGGAAGGAGAAGAUUGAAGCAGAACUUGCCAAGGAAAGGGCCCAACACUUGGUUGAAUUUGAAGAGCAAGCUCUUCUCUUUAAGGAAGAAACAAAAUUGCAACUUGAUAUUGAAAAAGAAAAACACCAAGAUGUAAUCCAAAAGUAUAAGAAAGAACAAGAGGAACUACAAAUGAAGAUAUCUGACUUAAUCACAGGCGCUACAAGAGAUCUAAGGCAGGAAGUGACCACUCUUAAAGAAAAACUUCACAAAUCCCAUAUUCGGUACACUGAAGAAUCUAAUUCAAAGGAAAAAGAAAUUGAAAAUCUUAAAAAUUUGGUUGCAGAAUUUGAAUCUCGCUUGAAGAAGGAAAUUGACAGUAAUGAUUCAGUUUCAGAAAACUUGAGGAAGGAAAUGGAACAGAAGUCGGAUGAACUGAAAAGAGUAAUGCUGGCUCAAACACAACUGAUAGAGCAAUUUAACCAGUCCCAGGAAGAGAAUACUUUUCUUCAGGAGACAGUGCGUAGAGAAUGUGAAGAACGCUUUGAACUGACAGAGGCUUUGAGUCAAGCCAGAGAACAGCUCCUGGAGCUCAGUAAGCUUCGUGGAAGUUUACCAUUCUCACCGUGUUCCCUCAGCAAGGGCAGCCUAACCUCCCCUGCUGCAGCAGUCAGUAAUCAUGGAGAGAGAAGCCUUGCAAGACUGAACUCUGAAAAAGGAAUCCAAAUUCCCAACCUGCGCGGGGUGUCAAAACCCACCACUUUCCCAACCUCAGAUAAGCCGAAGAGGGUUAGAUCAGGCGUGCCCAUUCUCCCCCAGCCACAUCCUCCCAGGGGUGGAGCAUCUUCAGCAAAUGAGACUAGACAGAGACUGGCUGCCAUUCUUAGGAGAAGGCGGAGUCAGCAAUGAUCCAAAAUGAGGAGCAGGAAGCUCCCUACAGCGUGCACGCUCUUUCAGAGAGUGCCAGGAAUUCACUGUAACUGAGAAUGACAAUGAUAAAAUUAUUUUCACAGAUCAGGAAGGCAUACCUAUAGAUGUAUUUAACAAAAGACUGUAAAAAGCUGGAAAAUUGUGAAGCCUUAUUUUUCAAGAGGGUUUUGAUAGAGUAACAGAUCAUUAAGUUGUUGGUAUUCCAGAGGUCCGAUUUCUAUGUUUAUGUUGGAAUGUGCUCUAUGAAUAUAGCCUUUUAGAGAUCACAGGUAAAAUUUUUCACCCAUAACAUCUUUUCAAUUUCUUGCGCCACUACAAGCAGAUAUAUUUCCACAAAAAAAUAGAUUGUUUGAGAUUU